GUGCGCCGGAAGAGCACGCCCAGUCCGGGCUGCGCGGAGGAAGCGCUGGGGUCCCGGAGGGCGGGGGUGGCGGCGCCGGAGGUCGCCAUGGCUACCGAGCCCGAAGCCGCGGAGCCGGUGGUGCCUUCGCUCGUGGAUCGAUACUUCACUCGCUGGUACAAACCGGAUGUCAAAGGAAAAUUUUGUGAGGACCACUGUAUACUACAGCACUCUAACCGAAUAUGUGUCAUCACAUUGGCAGAAUCUCAUCCAGUUCUUCAAAGUGGAAAAACAAUUAAAAGCAUUUCCUAUCAGAUCAGUACCAACUGUAGCAGACUUCAGAACAAGGUCUCUGGGAAAUUUAAGCGGGGGGCACAGUUUCUAACAGAGCUUGCACCUCUCUGUAAGAUUUACUGCUCAGAUGGUGAAGAAUAUACUGUGUCUAGUUGUGUUAGAGGACGUUUGAUGGAAGUGAAUGAAAACAUCCUCCAUAAGCCAUCUAUUCUUCAAGAAAAGCCAUCUACUGAAGGCUACAUUGCAGUUGUGUUACCCAAAUUUGAAGAAAGUAAAAGCAUAACAGAAGGGUUACUGACACAAAAACAAUAUGAAGAAGUCAUGGUGAAACGCAUUAAUGCCACAACAGCUACGUCAUGAGGAUUGACAUGGAACAAAAAGCAAAGUGGGAUUCUUGUUACCUGGCCUAAACCAUCAGGGUACUAAAGGAGAAGAACCAGUAUAUGUAAAGCAUACCUAACAGCCAGCCAUAUGCAGGGGAGGCCUAGUGCUUCACUUAGUUUUCCCUCUCUGUCUUCAUAAUGAGCCUUGGUUCCCAUUUGUCUACAGCCUGCCAGAUCUGGCCUGCCCAUGUACUCACACUGUUCUCUUGCAUCUCUCUAACAACUGGCAUGCAAGGCAUGUUUUUCUGAUUAAAAACAAACAAAGCUCUUUGAAGAAGAUUUAGAAAAUACAGAAGAGUUUUAAGUAGCCAAGUAAAAAUAAUUUACCCAUCAUCCCAUAAUCCAGAAGUAAAUACAUUUGACCCUUGAGCAACAUAGGUUUGAACUGCAAGGGUCCACUUAUGCAUGGACUAUUUUCAACUAUAAACGAGUCAAAAAUAUAUCAUUAACCAAACACGAAACCCACUUAUAGAGCAGGUUCAUAUACUCAGGUUCCAAAGGGCCAACUGCAGGACUUGAGUUCUCACGUAUGGAUUUGGGUAUAUGUGGAAGUUCCUGGAACCAAUCCCCUAUGUAAACCAAGGGAUAACUACUACAUUUUAACCUACUUCUGUUUGAACAUAUGGUAUGGUUAUUGCUUUUGCCUCGUUUUCCUAACAGUUUGAAGUUUAAAAAAACCUAACCCACCUUUCUUACCCAGUCUUCUAUAAUGUGCCUACCAAAAAGCCUAGUCCUAGCCCAUCUGCCUCAACUCCUCUCCCUUUUAGGUUGUAGGGAAGAGGCCGGAGUGUAGAGUAUAUUAUAUCUUCUGUCCCCCUUAUGCCAACAAGAUGGCCUUCCCCUCUGAAACAAAGUAAAACUGCAACACUGUGACUUCUUAAAUGAGGGAUAUGUGAAAAGGCUAUGAAAAAUACAAAGGCUUUCCUAGGAAAUGUGUUAUAAUGCAGCGGGAAGCUAAUUCUUGAAAUAUGCACAUUAUAGUUACUCAGUCUCACAUACUCUAGUUACUGGCAAAGAAGUUACUGAGAAUAUGUCAUUCAAAGGCAUAGGGGCCUUUGAAUGGAACAAAUGCUUUCACAUCAUUUAAAGUAAAAAAAAACCUCCAACAACUGUGAAUUUAUAGUUUAAGAGUGAUUUACACUGAAUUUCAAAUAAAAGGACUAUAAAACGUGUUAUUUUUCUGUAAGGGCUAUAACAUACAUGUCAAUAUCACUGUUUUUAAAUAAAAUAUACUUUUAUACAGAA